UGUUUUCAUAAUAGCUAUCCUAAUGGGGUGAAGUGGUAUCUCAUUAUGGUUUUGAUUUGCAUUUUUCCAAUUGAUUAGUGAUGUCGAGCAUCAUUUUAUGUGUCUCAAGACUCUUGAAAAUUAUGGGUUUCUGGAUAGAAGAGUAUGCAUAUGUUCAUUACAUUUUGCAUAACAACUAAGGGGAAGGCAUCACAAACCCCUGAAGCCCAUAGGAAAACAACUGAGUUAGGUUUAGAGCCCUUCUUAUGGGAGGAACACUGUGGUUAGGUGGCUGUCUCCAAGCCAUUGCUAUAAAGAGAAUGAACUGCAUGGUUUUAACUUUUGUUAAGAUGUGUGAGAAACUGACUGUUCUAAAUUGAAAUGCAAGUCUUUUGACACAGGAGCUUUUGUUCUUCAUGAUGUAGUUUUUGGGGUGAGAGACAAGAGACAGAAGGGAAGCCAGUCCUGGGAAAAUGAGUAGGGCUCUAGUUCAAUGGAAGUUUGUCUAAACAACAGAGAAGGGCAAAUGUUUUGUAUUUUAGGAUGAACUCCUGUAAGGAGGUGAGAGUCUGCUGCCUUUUUUCAAACCAAGAGCUCAAGCCAUACCGGGAAAGGACAAGUAAUAUGUGAAUUCUUCUAAGGAAAGGUCCAAGCAAGGUCUAAGGCUUGGAAUGUCUAAGCUGAGUGAGGAAAGUGUGGGUAGCCUGAAAACAGAGAUGGGAAGCCCAGGCAACGGAGACUGGAGAUUCAGUCAAUUAGUCAAUUAGUCAAGCAGCUAAGUGAGUCAUGGAGGAGGUCUGGAAGCACUGGAGCAAGACAGAAUACUCUUCCUCUCCAGGAUCAAUCAAAUAAUCCUAGGGGAUGAGACAAAAAACCUUUUCUUCAGUAGUAAUAGAACCUUGAUUUGGGACGGCCUUGGUGAUUGCAGGAGCUGGUUAUCUGGGGAGGUGGUUCUCAACCUUGGGCGUACAUUAUAAUUACCUGGGGAGCUUUGCAAAUCCCAGUGGCCCAGACAGGCUGCAGACUCAUUAAAUCAGAAUCUCUGUGGAGGGGAGGUGGGAACCAGGCAUUAGUAUUUUCUAAAGCUCUCCAGGUGACUCUGAAAUGCAGCCAAAGUGAGAACCUCUGAUUUAGGGGCAGACAGUCAGACAGUCAUUAUGCCAUCCUGAUUGGUUCUCAAAUAAUUCUGAAUGUGGUUGAAACCAGGCUACUCAGUCGAAUCAUUUCUUGCAUCUCUCUCCACUCAUUCAGGGGAAGGCUUUCUUGGCCUAGUUGUCAAAAGUUCCUACACUGGGCCGGUGCUUUUCAAACUUUUAUGUGCAGACGAAACAUCUAUGGGUUGUAAUGUAGUAGGUCCAGCCUGAUAAUUGGCAUUUCUCACAAGCACUCAGGUGAUGCUGUUGCUGCUGCACCAUACUGUGAGUAGCAGCAUUCUAGACUCAUAACCAUUGAGUUGAUUUUACUUAUUGUUUUAUUCAUCAGAUUAUUGAAAGGUGCUUACUACCUGCAAGAUACUGUGCUAGUUAGGUACUGGGGAUGUGGUUAUGGACACAAAAGAGACACCACCUGCCCUCAAGGAUCAUAAAAUCUAGGAGAAAAGGCAAUGAACCUAUUAUUUCACCAAAAAAUUACCUAAAUACAAUUAGAGUAAGGGCCACAAAGGAAAAGUGUAGGCUGCUAUGAAAUCCUGUGAUAAGGAGCCUUGAUCUCGUUAGUAGGACAUGAUUACGACUCAAGGGAUAAAGAAAGCCCCAGGAGACCCAUGUUAUGUUCUGAUGCUCACUCUGGCUGUGGGAACCCAUUGACUUCUUCCAGUUGCACUGGCUAUAUUUAGUUUAUUGACCCUUCUUUCCUGCGGUACAUUUUCCCAUGGUGGCCUCAGCCAUUCCUUGGCUUUAUCUACCCGAUCUCAACUUCUGCCUCUCCUCUGGGCUCUAGCUUUGGGUUUCUAAUUAUUGAGGCACAUCUCCAACUAGUGGACAUGCUAGCAUCUAAAACCCAAACUAUUCUGGGACAAACUCUUCACCUUCUUCACUAAACCAGCACUUCUUCAAUAUUUCUGACAGUGUCACCACCAUUCUUUAAGCCAGUGAGGCAAAAUUCAACAUAUCCUUUUUUUUUUUUUUUUGAGAGAGAGUCUUGCUCUGUCUCCUAGGCUGGAGUGUAAUGGAGUGAUCUUGGCUCACUGCAACCUCUGCUUCCCAGGUUCAAGCGAUUCUCCUGCCUCAGCCUCCUGAUUAGCUGGGAUUACAGGUGUGCACCACCAUGCUCGGCUAAUUUUUGUAUUUUUAGUAGGGACGGGGUUUUGCCAUGUUGGCCAGGCUGGUCUCAAAAUCCUGACCUCAGGUGACCCGCCUGCCUUGGCCUCCCAAAGUGCUGGGAUUACAGGUGUGAGCCAUGGUGCCUGGCCAACAUAUUCUUUUAACUAUAUACUUUACUAUUGUCGGCCCAAGGAUACAGCACUUAUUUUUGAUAUGGGACCUGAAAUAGAUGUAUAUUGCAUUUGCUUGAUUCAUAGGUGACUAAGUUGAAUAAAUAGCCCACUGUAGACACUCAGCAAAUGUUAUUUACGUAAGUGAGGCCUGGGGGGAGGAGGAAAGGGACCUAACACUCAUUUUUUCCAUGUAUUCUUGCUAGAUAUUUUAUGUAUCUUCGCUCAUUUAUUCCUCCCAAUAGCUUUCUAGAACUUUAUUAAGUGAGGCUUGUAGAGUGUCCAGAGAGUGCGUGAUAGCAGCAUGUAAACGUAGUUUUUUUCAGUUUCAGAAAACAUCAUGUUCUUUUGCUAGGCUUCAUACCUUGUACAUGGUAAAGUGAUCUCUAAACUCUUAUUAUUAUAAAUAUGUUUUGAAAAAUAAAAGCUCUUUCAAAUAUUAGCUAUGAAUUUUUUUCCUCAAAUUUGGAAAAUGUAUUAAUAAACUGUAUCUGAUGAAAUGAAGCUUAGUUACUUUAAAACAACUGUGUCUAGCCUGCUUCAUGUACUCAAUACAUAUGAGUUCCCUUUCAUAGAUUCAAAUACUCUGUUUUGGUUUUCUUUGUAUUUUUCUGUCUUUUUCCUUUUCGUGUUUUACCCUGGGCAUUUUCUAUUGAACUAUUAUCUUCUAGAUCACCAAUUCUCUCUUCAGCUGGGUCUUUUUGCUGUAACCCAUCUAUAGCAUUCUUAAUUUCUUCUAUUACAUUGUAUUUUUCAGUUCUAGAAUUUCCAUCUGACUCAUAUAUAUGAAUAUAUAUGUAUUAUAUAUAUUCUAGUUCUUUGGUGAAAUUGUCACCCAUUUUCUUAAACAUGUUAAUUAUUUUAAAGUCUAUGCCUGAUAAUCCCAAUAUCUAGAUCACCUGUGAAUCUGUUUCUGUUGUCUGCUUUUUUUUCCUAUUGGUUCUAUCUCUUGGUAUGCCCGGUAAUUUUUAAUUGAAUGUUGGGCACUGUAAAUAAAAAAUGAUGGAGGCUCUUGAUGGUGUAUUCUUCAACCGAGGAGUGUUCUUUUUGAGCUUCUGGUAGGCAGUUAAAAUUUUUAUAAUCUCAACUCAAUCUCCCUACCCAGGUGUAGCCUUUUAGGAGUCCCAAAUGAAAGCCCAGAUUAGAUACCCAGGUCUGUCCACUUUGGUAGGCCCUGAACUCCAAUUAUUGUCUCUUCAUCAGUGGGGACAGCUGUGCUUAGUUUAUCAUCCCUCUAGCAGCUGUUUUCUCCUUUGCUUCCCUUUCUGCUUGUGAAAUUUACACAUCAGUAAAUACCUCAGUGGUGGUGGUGGGGAGAGAGUGUUGGGUGGCUUCUGUGUGUCCUUACUCUGGGAGUUUGGACUUUCAGGUUAUGGUUGUCUUGGUAACACCUAGAUGCCCUCAAAGAGAUGUUAAUGUUUAAAUUUUAUCCAGUUUUUAAAAUAUGCUUAUCUAUUAUUGCUGGAAUGAGACAUGUAUUCUCUGUUUUUUAGGCUUUAAAAUUUAAGUAAGGAGACUUGCUUUUGAUUCAUCACAGUGCCCCAGAAACAGGUGUCAUUUAAACGUGCAGGUGAGAGAUCAUUGUUUGCCUUGCAGUCUAGUCUGCUCCCUGCUCAUCCCACAAGAACCUUUGAUUUUUCAUAACUUUUUGCUUUGCAUUCUGAGGAAGAAACUUGACAAUUAGUGAAUUGAAUAUUAUUGAUGUUAUCAGAUGUAGAAUGGUUGCUUUAUUUAGCAGGGAACAGGGUUAAAUAAAUGAUAGAGACAAUAACUCAGGAGGCUCAGAUCCCUAUUUUCAUCUUCCAGAUAGUAAGAAAGAACAGUAAUUCUUCCACAAAGGAAGUGAAGGCCAUGAUGAUUUCUAGUGGCUUUGUCAUGCUGAUGUUUUUGCUAUACUCUGUACUUUUGAGGGGUUGCAAAUUUGAAGGAUGCGGUAGUGAUUUUUUGAAGUGUUUUUCAUGUUACUUUUCUGCAUUUAUAUAUAUGCAUAGAUAAUGUGUAUGUAUAUAAAUGCACAUACUGUACACAGCUCCUUGUUUUGUGUCCCCUUUUCUCAAAAAAGCAUUGAAUGCAAAAACAUAAGUUCUCCUCAGUCACAACCUCUAAGAAAGGAAAGAAAAUUUAGAGCCAGAAGUUGUUAACCUCAGCAGGAGUUUAUGACUGUAAGAUUUCAUCACCUUACUGUCUUAUCUGGUAUAGUUACAUCUGCCCCAAUUUAUUUAUUUUCCUGCUUCCUUCUCUGCCAGUAAUGAGCCUGGAACUUGAAGGAGGGCAAGGUACAUUCCUUGUGGUAUUUAUGAGGGAGGAGACCCAUGUCUUUGGAAAGUGGACGUUGGCAUAAAUGCUUUCCUUCAUGGGGGGUGAAUUUUCCUACUUAAGUUCACUAGCUAGCCCGUGCAUUCGCCCUCUUCCUCCUCUCCAUGUUAUUCUUGUUGGCGAAAGUGUAUGAUGUACUUUCUGUUUCUAAGAUAGAAAAUAUGAUGUACUUUCUGUUUCUAAGAUAGAAAGUGUAUGAUGUACUUUCUGUUUCUAAGAUAGAAAGUGUAUGAUGUACUUUCUGUUUCUACGAAACUUGGAGUUUACUUGUGGGGAAAGUCAAAGACACAUGAACAUUGAAAUAUUAGUAGAAACAAUUAAAUAGCAACAGAAGUUAAUAAAAGGCGAAGGGCUAAAUGGAAUGCACAGAACCUGCUGUGGAAGAGGGAAACCAAAGGGCAGUUUCUCAUUGACCACAUCUGCAACUACUACAGCCUGCUGGAGAAGGACUACUUUGGCAUUCGCUAUGUGGACCCAGAGAAGCAAAGGCACUGGCUUGAACCUAACAAGUCCAUCUUCAAGCAAAUGAAAACUCAUCCACCAUACACCAUGUGCUUUAGAGUGAAAUUCUACCCACAUGAACCCUUGAAGAUUAAAGAAGAGCUCACAAGAUACCUUUUAUACCUUCAGAUUAAAAGGGACAUUUUUCAUGGCCGCCUGCUGUGCUCCUUUUCUGAUGCUGCCUACCUGGGUGCCUGUAUUGUUCAAGCUGAGCUUGGUGAUUACGAUCCUGAUGAGCAUCCUGAGAAUUACAUCAGUGAGUUUGAGAUUUUCCCCAAGCAGUCACAGAAGCUGGAAAGAAAAAUAGUGGAAAUUCAUAAAAAUGAACUCAGGGGGCAGAGCCCACCAGUUGCUGAAUUUAACUUGCUCCUGAAAGCUCACACUUUGGAAACCUACGGGGUGGAUCCUCACCCAUGCAAGGAUUCAACAGGCACAACAACAUUUUUAGGAUUCACAGCUGCAGGCUUUGUGGUCUUUCAGGGAAAUAAGAGAAUCCAUUUGAUAAAAUGGCCAGAUGUCUGCAAAUUGAAGUUUGAAGGGAAGACAUUUUAUGUGAUUGGCACCCAGAAGGAGAAAAAAGCCAUGUUGGCAUUCCAUACUUCAACACCAGCUGCCUGCAAACAUCUUUGGAAGUGUGGAGUGGAAAACCAGGCCUUUUAUAAGUAUGCAAAAUCCAGUCAGAUCAAGACUGUAUCAAGCAGCAAGAUAUUUUUUAAAGGAAGUAGAUUUCGAUAUAGUGGGAAAGUUGCCAAAGAGGUGGUGGAGGCCAGUUCCAAGAUCCAGAGGGAGCCUCCUGAGGUGCACAGAGCCAACAUUACUCAGAGCCGCAGUUCCCACUCCUUGAACAAACAGCUCAUCAUUAACAUGGAACCCCUGCAGCCCCUGCUUCCUUCCCCCAGCGAGCAAGAAGAAGAACUUCCUCUGGGUGAGGGUGUUCCAUUGCCUAAAGAGGAGAACAUUUCUGCUCCCUUGAUCUCCAGCUCCCCAGUGAAGGCAGCCCGGGAGUAUGAAGAUCCCCCUAGUGAAGAGGAAGAUAAAAUAAAAGAAGAACCUUUAACCAUCUCUGAACUAGUGUACAACCCAAGUGCCAGCCUGCUCCCCACCCCUGUGGAUGACGAUGAGAUUGACAUGCUCUUUGACUGUCCUUCUAGGCUUGAGUUGGAAAGAGAAGACACAGAUUCAUUUGAGGAUCUGGAAGCAGAUGAAAACGCCUUUUUGAUUGCUGAAGAAGAGGAGCUGAAGGAGGCUCGCCGUGCUUUGUCGUGGAGCUAUGACAUUCUGACUGGCCAUAUUCGGGUGAACCCACUGGUCAAGAGUUUUUCCAGGCUCCUUGUGGUGGGCCUGGGACUGCUGCUCUUUGUAUUUCCCCUGCUCCUCCUCCUUUUGGAGUCAGGUAUUGAUCUCUCCUUCUUAUGCGAAAUCCGCCAGACACCAGAGUUUGAGCAGUUUCACUAUGAAUACUACUGUCCCCUCAAGGAGUGGGUGGCUGGGAAAGUCCACCUCAUCCUCUACAUGCUGGGUUGCUCAUGAAGUUAAUCUCUCACGUGACUAAGGGCUAUAUUCAAUGCUAGUGAUUUCUUUUUUUCAGCAAAUGCCUGGUUCUGAAGGGUCACGGGGCUGUCAACAGGUGUUCCUUACUCAUAAUUGAUUAUUCAAACCUUUAAGUUAGCUUUCCAUAAUUCACUGCACUUAAAUAAGUUUAAAUCAAAUACAGUUAUUUUAGUUACAGGUUAGGAAGAUGGUCUUUAAAUAACCAAAAAUAUGUUUAUUUUUUAUUAUAGUGUAGACAUACCCUUCAUCUAUUAUAUCAUAAUACAUGUUACAUUGGACUGAAUUAGAUUUUCCCAUUUCUAAUAGUUGGCACCAUUAUAAGCUAUAAGGUUCAGAAUCAGAAUUUUAGUAACAACUCAAGAGAAAGUUGUUGAAUAUAAUCCUUAGUGAAAACAGUGUCCUCUAACCAAUGCCUAUACAACUAAAUUUAUGCUGGGUUUUUGGUUCUGUUUUUUUAAAAAUAUUUUUAUGUGUUCAAACUAUUUUGGUAAAUUUUUAGCAAAAAAAAAAAAGAAGCCUCCUGGAGUUAUUUACAUGUACAGAUUGUAAGACUAAUGCACAAAAGGUAUAUCAGAAUUUUUUUAAUGUUUUGGCGCUACUUUGUUUUUAAAAAUAUUUUUGGCUGAACAAUACCAUAAUUUGUUAUGAUCUGCAUAGGAGAUAGAAAAUGGGUAGAAAGACACUAUAGUAAGUAAGCUGCUAAAACAGAGGAUGGAACUGGAGGAUGUAGAAACUGAGAGCAUCAAGUGGACUCAGGGUGGUCCAUUUUUCAAAGUAUUUGGACAAGAGGACUUGUUAUUUUCAUUUGUAUUCUGUCCGUAUAUUUUGGCUGGAGAAGCAGAUGUUUUAAAAAGAAAGUGAGAGUUUAAAGGAAAAAAGGUAACAGAUGUGCUAGUCAGUUGCAUAUCAAUGUACAUUAACCCAAGAGUGAAGGCAGAUAGGAACUGGAGAAAUGGAAAGUGGCAAAAAUGAGUUCUGGUGAGGCUGGCAGGCAAAUGGUGACAGGCGAAUGGUCUAUUUUAUGAAAGUGAUGGUGAUGCCAGCGUUCGAUGAUGUGAAGAGCAGUGCAGUCGCUGUCUGAGUUAACAUGAACAUGUUUAAGUGGAUCUAAAUAAAAGUGGAGAAACUUUAAGGUAAAUAUUUUGAUCCCUCAUGCCAUUUGUUGUGAUUCUGUAGAAGAAACUUCAAAAAUGUGUUUGUAUGUGAGUGUGCGUGUGUGUGUGUGUGAGAGAGAGAGAGAGAGAGAGAGAGAGAAUAUGAAUGGCUUUUUGAUACAUGUCCAUGAUCAUGUUUUGCGGUGGUCAUUAUACUCCUUUCCUUUCCCAGUUGUUUUAAAAUUUGACUUCCAUAGAGAAACUGGAGAGGCCUCAUGAGAUGACAUACCAGUUCAGCCUGGGUAAAGUAGUGACAUGACCCUAACCAGACUGUAGAGGGGACCAGUGCUCUAGUACCUUCCUUGAUACCAUUAAAUCCAUGAUGGAAAGGAUUUAAUCCAACAAUUUAAUGGUAUCAAGGAAGGUACUAGAGCAUUGUACCAUCAGCAACGUACUGAUGCCUUCCCAUGCAGACUACCUGCUGAUACUGUGUUAUGUGGGAGAAAGAUAAGAGUCUAGAACUUAUGCCAUGGAGCAUAGAGCUUCUCUGUGGAUUGAAAACAUUCCACUGCCCUAAUGUACAAAGUUACAGGGCCCACUUGGAAUCGCUCUCUCUAGCUAAUGACAUUCCAACCCUAUCAUUAGCAUGAUUUCUAAAUUGGGCAAUACAUUUCCACUCACUCAGUGGAGCUCUGAGUACUUCACUGGACAUUUAAUUUUGGAAAUGAGUUUUGAAACUCAGUUCGUGAAGCCUGCAGUCGAGCAAAUGACUAUAUAUUUGCCAUUAAGUUUGAGGGGUUUCCUUUCCUAUAUGCUUUCAGUGAUUUAUUUUGCUUUUUAAAUAAAGAUUGUUUGUUUAUUACCUGAAAGUUGAUACUGAUUUAGGAAUAUAUUUUCUGUGAUUGGAAUCCUCAACAAUUUAUUUUGGAAGCUUGCAGAUGGCUAGGUUUGAAAUUGAAAUUUGUGUUUUUCUCCUUCUUUUCUCAUACGACUUCUAAGUCAUCCUUUCUGACAUAAGGCAACUUUAGUGUAGUCUGCACAAAAUUAGUCCCCUUCUGAUCAUGCGUCAUAUAAUUUUCUCUAAAGUUCUGACUAUGACAAAUCAUCUGGCCCUCAGUCUUUCAAAAUAAUAUUAUAUAAUAUUUUUUAAAUUAUGGAACUAAUAUAUUUUCCAUUGUAAAAUACUUAAAAAAUAUGAUAGUAUAAAUAUCACAUGUAAUCCAACGAUGCAGAUUUAUCUUAAGGAGUAAUAAAUAUAUUAUUUUAACAUUUCCAGCUAACAUCUCUUUUCUCUUAGGUGGAAACUUCAUUGUUGAAUAGAAAUGUUUUUAAGUGAAGAAGUUGACAGAAUAGGGUCUGCUGAAUUUAAACAGCCAUCAAAAGUUAAACUGGAAUCUUGAAAUGCCAUUUGCUCGGCAUAGAAUCAGAGCCUUUUAGAAACAUCCAUUUAAGUUUUGUUAGAAGAUAGUCACCAGUUGCCUGAAUCGAAUGAGGAAAAGCCUGCUUCCAGAGAUGGACAGUAUAUUAUAGAGUGAGAUAUAGAGUUUAAAGCAAGUGUGUGAGUAUAUGUAUAUUCCAUAUUAUUGGUAUAUGUGUGUUUAUAUAUGAAUCUGUAUAUAUGUGUGUCUUUGAAUAGACACAACAUAUAUGCCCCUCAUGCAUAAUUGUGCUUAUUUUGCCCUAAUUGAGGAAUUUGAGAUGUAUUAUUGGUUCUUCUCCCUCUCAGAUACUAUGGUGGGUAAAACCCACAGCCUGAAAGGGUUAAAUUUUCCAUAAAUGCCACUGAGUGUACAUUUGUGGAUAUAAAUAAAUAUAUAUAAUACACACACACAUAUGGCAAAUACAUAUACACACACAAUAUUGCCUUUAGUGCUAAUGCAAGUUGGAUCAUGAAAACAAUGUAGGUAAAGUAAAGUAUGUAUUUGUCUGUGCUUGAAAAAUAUUGUAAAAUGUUAUGUAUUUGGAAUAUAUUUUGUGGUUUGUCUAAUAUUUAUAAACACAACUCGGGGUGAAUUCACAAUGAGUUUAUUUCAUUGAAAUACUAGAGAUAUGGGGGCCAUGUUACUGUGAUUGGAGCCUUACCUUUGUAUAGUGAAAUUUGCAUUUCUAUGUCAACAUCCAGAUUGUUUUAUAUGUUAAUAUGGUGGCAGGAAUCCCUAAUAAAAAUACUCUGGGGUAAAA